GUCACCGCUUUCGCUUCUGCUUGAUAUAUGUUUAAUAGACCAUACAGCAGAAAAUUGGAGGCCGAAGCUGACAAAAUUGGACUACUGCUUGCUGCAAAGGCUUGUGCAGACAUAAGAGCCAGUUCAGUGUUUUGGCAGCAAAUGGAGUUCGUUGAUAGCCUGCAUGGCCAACCCAAGAUGCCAGAAUGGUUAUCUACACACCCUUCUCAUGGCAAUCGAGUUGAGUACUUGGAUAGACUUAUACCUCAGAUUUGGUGAGUCUUGAAUGCCCCUGAAAACCAUUCUGCUCCAUUUCAAAAGUACUUCCCAGUCUUCGUAUUUUACCUAAAUGCAAAUUCACUGCCUUGGAGAGUGUGAGUCCAAGAAGAAAUCCUUUGGGCUAUUUCCUUGGCUUCUCUCCAUGACGAUUCCUGACUCGUGGCCCCGGCAAUCUUGGGAAGACAUCAUCCAGCUUCUUCAGUCCAGACCCUGGGCACCCCCCUUUUGCCAGGAUCGUCCCCACCCAGCCUGGACACAUUGACUGAACUGUUUUCUAGGACACUGCACUCAGCAAGACAUGGUGGUGAGCCCUGACUCUCAGUCUUCAUGAUUGAAGAACUCUUUUGUACAACACAAAGCACUCAAAAAGAGUGAAUGAAAUGUGCAGCUCAGAGUGUCAUUUCUGAAGGGAGGAGUCUUUCUCUUGGAGAAGAGUCCUCAAUGAGCCUGGCCGAGGCCCGGGAUCUGUGUGAAGUGGACUAAGGAUUAAGUAGGAUGUCAACUGAGACAGAACUUCAAGUAGCUGUGAAAACCAGCGCCAAGAAAGACUCCAGAAAGAAAGGUCAGGAUCGCAGUGAAGCCACUUUGAUAAAGAGGUUUAAAGGUGAAGGGGUCCGGUACAAAGCCAAAUUGAUCGGGAUUGAUGAAGUUUCCGCAGCUCGGGGAGACAAGUUAUGUCAAGAUUCCAUGAUGAAACUCAAGGGCGUUGUUGCUGGCGCUCGUUCCAAAGGAGAACACAAACAGAAAAUCUUUUUAACCAUCUCCUUUGGAGGAAUCAAAAUCUUUGAUGAGAAGACAGGGGCCCUUCAGCAUCAUCAUGCUGUUCAUGAAAUAUCCUACAUUGCAAAGGACAUUACAGAUCACCGGGCCUUUGGAUAUGUUUGUGGGAAGGAAGGGAAUCACAGAUUUGUGGCCAUAAAAACAGCCCAGGCGGCUGAACCUGUUAUUCUGGACUUGAGAGAUCUCUUUCAACUCAUUUAUGAAUUGAAGCAAAGAGAAGAAUUAGAAAAAAAGGCACAAAAGGAUAAGCAGUGUGAACAAGCUGUGUACCAGACAAUAUUGGAAGAGGAUGUUGAAGAUCCUGUGUACCAGUACAUUGUGUUUGAGGCUGGACACGAGCCAAUCCGUGAUCCCGAAACGGAAGAAAACAUUUAUCAGGUUCCCACCAGCCAAAAGAAGGAAGGUGUUUAUGAUGUGCCAAAAAGUCAACCUGCUGUGACCCAAUUAGAACUUUUUGGGGACAUGUCCACACCCCCUGAUAUAACCUCUCCCCCCACUCCUGCAACUCCAGGUGAUGCCUUUAUCCCAUCUUCAUCUCAGACCCUUCCAGCGAGUGCAGAUGUGUUUAGUUCUGUACCUUUCGGCACUGCUGCUGUACCCUCAGGUUACGUUGCAAUGGGCGCUGUCCUCCCGUCCUUCUGGGGUCAGCAGCCCCUCGUCCAACAGCAGAUGGUCAUGGGUGCCCAGCCACCAGUCGCUCAGGUGAUGCCGGGGGCUCAGCCCAUCGCAUGGGGCCAGCCGGGUCUCUUUCCUGCCACUCAGCAGCCCUGGCCAACUGUGGCCGGGCAGUUUCCGCCAGCCGCCUUCAUGCCCACACAAACUGUUAUGCCUUUGCCAGCUGCCAUGUUCCAAGGUCCCCUCACCCCCCUUGCCACCGUCCCAGGCACGAGUGACUCCACCAGGUCAAGUCCACAGACCGACAAGCCCAGGCAGAAAAUGGGCAAAGAAACGUUUAAGGAUUUCCAGAUGGCCCAGCCUCCGCCCGUGCCCUCCCGCAAACCCGACCAGCCCUCCCUCACCUGUACCUCAGAGGCCUUCUCCAGUUACUUCAACAAAGUCGGGGUGGCACAGGAUACAGACGACUGUGAUGACUUUGACAUCUCCCAGUUGAAUUUGACCCCUGUGACUUCUACCACACCAUCGACCAACUCACCUCCAACCCCAGCCCCUAGACAGAGCUCUCCAUCCAAAUCAUCUGCAUCCCAUGCCAGUGAUCCUACCACAGAUGACAUCUUUGAAGAGGGCUUUGAAAGUCCCAGCAAAAGCGAAGAGCAAGAAGCUCCUGAUGGAUCACAGGCCUCAUCCAACAGUGAUCCAUUUGGUGAGCCCAGUGGGGAGCCCAGUGGUGAUAAUAUAAGUCCACAGGCCGGUAGCUAGAUAGCGCAGGUCUGGGAGCCAGAGCCUCUGUACGCGCAGAUCAACAGACCUAAGAAAUAGCAUCGAUGCGAGCUCGUGGUGGGUGCUCAAGACUGGCAUGGACAUCAGCAUCACGACAGGCUCUCUUGUAUUCUUUCACCUCUUCCCACAAGAAAUUCAUGAUUGCCCAAUGGAACUCGCUCAGAAGAGGGAACUAAGCAUUUUUGGCAACCAAUGGCAGAUAUCUAUGGCAGCACACAAAAAAAGUAUAGAAAGAUCCACCCAACAUUAAAUCAGAAAUCAAGCAAAUGCUUACCCAACAAAUAUUUGAGCCCUCAUAGCUGGGUUUAAGAUGACUCAGUGUGCAAAAUUAUUAAUUCCCUUUUUAUUUCUCUACCUGUUGACCACUGUUGAGACACCAAAUUUGGAGUGACAGGCAUCAGAGGAUUACAACAGGGUUGGAACUGACUUCUUUAAGCAAAAGCAAAGGGUCUUCUGUGACCACAAUAUCGUCAUCCAUAUGCCUUUUCACAUAGGAUGAUGUGUUUUUUGUCACUCCAUGGGGCCUGGUCUGCCAUUUUCCCCCCUUUCCUUUUUUUGUCAUGUUUGAAAAUUAAUAGGUGUACAAAUUUUUGUAUUGCUUUUGACUUUUUUUAGAUAUGGGUGAAGAAAUCUAACUGGGGAGAAAAAAAGCCUCAGUGAAAUGAAUUAACUUGAAAUUACAAGACAAAUAAGUGGUUGAUUAUUCAUUAUGAUCACGAAUGUUGCCAAAACAGUCCUUUAGCUAUUCUGCAUCCUGGUGAAGAAAGACAGCUUUCAGUACGAACCUUCAUUCUGUGAGUAGGAAAAGACAUCAGAUCCCAUUGAUGAGAAAGAUGAAAAAUGCAUCUGAUUUCUUAAGAAGCUCUAAACUCUAAGUACAAUAAAAUGAUAUUUUUUAUUUUUCCGAUAUCUUGCUGCUGUGUUGCUAUGCAGACAAGUGUCUUCUCCACGUGCCAUUUUCAAAGAAAAGUCAUUUGCCAAAUAAUUCUGGUACAAUUCUGGUAAUGUGGUUUUGGAUCUUAAAAACCAACUUUCUAAUGGAACAAUGGUGGCAUAAAUAUUCAGAAUAACAAACUGAUUCUGUGGUCCAAAUGGUUCAUCUCUAUCUCUUUUUGUACAUCAGAAAAUUCAAAUGGGAUUUUUAUUUUAUAACUUGAAAAAAAAACCUUACCAUUAAACUCUUUAAAUAUUUAAGGGAAAUGGCUUUAAGGAGUUCUAAUGAAAAAAAAUUGUCUUUUUUUUGUAAAUAUAAAUGUUAAUGAAAAUGAUUUUUAAUAAUGCCAUUACACUGUAGAGAAGGUAGCAGAUUGAGUGCAAGGUGUGACAAACUUGAUGGAUGGGGCUCACUUUCCAGACGUUAUUCUGGAGCAUAUGGUAGGAAGCUGGAGUGCAGGGACAGCUGGCAGGAGCAGUUGGCCAAUCAGCAGCUAGUGAACGGGAAGGGAGCACGUGACUCCAUCAUCUAGCCUUUCCACGAGAGUCCCCACCCUACGUGCAACACAAGAAAAAGACAAUUCACAUUCUGAAGAAUUCAGAUUCUGAAACUCUCCCACCUCCCCACUCCCACCUACCCCCGAUAUAAAUCACUGGACUGUUUGUACGUGAAACAGAAGAGGCUAAGCUUCCUUUUUUUACACUUAUGAGACAAAAAGUGCAGUGUUUGGUUCGUAUGUUUAGCACAUGAUUUUCAUAAAGAAUCUAUAUAUUUUUGCCCUACAGAGAAUUGUUAUACAGGUCAAGUGUGUUUUCCUGAUGUUCCUAUGCAGUUACAGUAUGUUGAAAGUGUUUUAACACUAAGAAGAAAACUUUAAAGAUUCAUGUGAUUAAUUGGAUUUGAGGAUAAUUAUUAUUAUUUGGUUUUUAGAUUUGAAAAGUAGAAUUUCCAUUGAGACAAUUGAUUUGAAUAGGCCUGCAUUUGAUUCUUCAUAUCAAUAGAAACUAAAAUGAUUUGGGAGAUUCAUUUGAAAAAUGAUUGUAUACUUGUUCACAAAGCGAAAAGUGAUACAUGAAGGUAAUGGUUAUCAUUUAAAGCCCACAUUUUACACUAUCAGGUCACAGGAGUCUAAUUUUUUUUUCAGUUAGAUAAACUGACCAAACGUCUAUUCAAGAAUAUAUGUCAAUAUCAUCCUAAUGUGGAAGGUCCGAAGAACCAGAAAAGUGAGAAGGGCCGUUUACCUCCCUCUGUAGCUAUCACCUGUUGGUCCACAGAGUUUCUUGAGAAAUGAGCAAACAUUUUAUGAUUAGGUAACCCUUUCACAUGAACGGGAAGAUGGGAAAGGUGGAAUGACCAUAAGAGUUGGCCUGAGACCAGUUUGUUUUCUGGGGAUUUGGUAAGAUAGGCAGUUCCCAUGGGAAAUUGCUUAAAUUGCUUUGUUGCCUAUGAUUUGAUUCUAAACAAGUGGUGCUAUCUUCUCCCUCAAUAUGGCUGUCUUGAGUUUGUCUUGCAGUAUCACACCAUUAUACCAAUUCUUUGGGUUGCUUCUGACACAUUCAAAGUGAACUCUGGCUGAUGUUGCUGUUUCAGGUAUACCAUCUGGAGUUAAUUUCCUAGCAGAAGGUGAAAGUCCAGGAGAAUUGUCCUCUUUCAUUGAACAUGAUUGAAAAUGUAACUGGCUCUGAACUUCAAGAAGAUAGAUGCCCAAGUGAUGCAUUAAAGUAAGGGAAAUAAAGUCAAGUUUUUCAACUGCCAUCCAUAUUCUCAUUGGCAGAAUUCUGAUUUUUUUCCAAGCACUGUUUGGUGAGCCUGGAAGCACCGUAUCCUGUCCCAGGAGUACAGUGAAAUUUCCAAGCAAGAGCUGAGGUGCCAAUACCAAAAGACCAUGGGGAGUCUGCACGGUUCUGGUUAGAUCAAUAGAAAAUCCAUGUGUACAACUGUUAAUUCCUCAUCCUCCACUAGCACUAAAUUUGUCACUUUAAAUUUUGAAACCAGGGAAACACCACCUGUCAUUCUGUCCCCAUUCUCCAUAGCUCUUCAAUCUUUACAUGCCGCAAGACUUUUUUGAUAGCUCGUACUCAUCCCAGUGUCUCCUGAAACCCCAUCAUGUAAUGUACUGGGCACCUUCUUUUAAACAAAUGUUUACUCUGUGGGUUUGGUUCAUUUCAAUUUCUGCGUUCUGACACAUAUUUUUUUAAUAAAGAUGAGAAAGAGAAAAUGACUGUUGCAGUACCUUUCUAGACCUACUUUAACUUUACCUCAGAUGACAGUUUGUUAACAUAUAUGGACACAUUAUUUUUAACUUUAUGUACAAUGCAUUCAACAGAACAGCAAAAUUUUUAGAAAUUUUCCAUUAAUUUCUGUAACACACCAUGUAAAACUGUUACAAAUAAACAUGUUUGAGAACAACA